AGUUGCUUUGCUGUUAGCCUGUUGGACCUUCGAGCCUAGCUGCUCGCACAGGACUCGGCCACCUGCCCUUCCUGCACCGACUGGCCAGGAGUUCAGAGCCUCAUGCUGAGCCAGGAGGAGCUCCGGGUGACGCAUACGGCAGGAUCGGGAUUGAGAGGCUGAAAAACUCAAGAGGUUUGGAUAUGGACCUUCUUCAAUUCCUGGCCUUCCUCUUUGUCCUGCUUUUGUCUGGGAUGGGAGCCACAGGCACCUUGAGGACCUCCCUGGACCCAAGCCUGGAGAUCUACAAGAAGAUGUUUGAGGUGAAGCGGCGGGAGCAGCUGUUGGCACUGAAGAACCUGGCACAGCUGAACGACAUCCACCAGCAGUACAAGAUCCUUGAUGUCAUGCUCAAGGGGCUCUUUAAGGUGCUGGAGGACUCCCGGACAGUGCUCACCGCUGCUGAUGUGCUCCCAGAUGGGCCCUUCCCCCAGGACGAGAAGCUGAAGGAUGCUUUCUCCCACGUGGUGGAGAACACGGCCUUCUUCGGCGAUGUGGUGCUGCGCUUCCCGAGGAUUGUGCACUAUUACUUUGACCACAACUCCAACUGGAACCUCCUCAUCCGCUGGGGUAUCAGUUUCUGCAACCAGACAGGCGUCUUCAACCAGGGGCCCCACUCGCCCAUCCUCAGCCUGAUGGCCCAGGAGCUGGGGAUCAGUGAGAAAGACUCCAACUUCCAGAACCCAUUUAAAAUCGACCGCACAGAGUUCAUUCCCAGCACUGACCCUUUCCAGAAGGCCCUGAGAGAAGAAGAGAAACGCCGAAAGAAAGAGGAGAAGCGGAAGGAGAUCCGAAAAGGCCCAAGGAUCUCCAGAUCCCAGUCUGAGUUAUAGCCCUGGAGCAGCUCAGGGCUCAGGGGGCCACAAGGAGGCAGGUCGGGAGGAAGAAGAGGUGGAGGUGUGGUUGUGGUGGAGAGCACCAGCUAGCCCCUUCCAGAAGGGGAGGCCACAUUUGCCCGGCCCCCUGGAGCUGGGUCUGAGCCCCAGCUGAAGGGACUGAGCCUCAGAUGGCUGGAUUUUCUCUCAGGGGCCUCCUGCUGAAGGGGCCUUCAGAGGAUUUUAUGCUGGAAAUAUGACCCUGUGCAGACUGCUGGGGGAGGCAGGAGGAUGCCUGCCUGGACCCUGUUGGUGGCUGAAGACCUCUGGCCAGCUGGCUUCCGCCCUUGGUGGGGAAGCAGCAGAACUAGGUUCUGAGCCACGGGUCAGGGUGCCACCCUGCUGCUGGCCCCACUGUGUCACAGAGCUGCCUGGCACAGGUCCCAGCCCCUCUGCAGAGACACAAUAAAAGCCAGCAGACCCUUUGGACCGACCAAGGCUGGUGGGGACACUGUGAGGGGACCAGGGCCCCUCAGGGAUGUAGAAACAGCUUGGAGGAUGCCUCUGCCCCACCAGGAGGGGCCCCAGGCCCUGGCAGGGCAGAGAAGGAAGGGGCUUGGCUUGGGCCUCCUGGUCCUACGCCAUCACUGCCCUUGACAAAUGAUUGGUGUUGGGAAAGGACCUGGAAGUGCCCUGGGACCUGGGAAACAUUUAGCUCAAGAAGACCUUGGAGCAACAUGAUCCCUGUCCUCAGAUGUCUGGGGACAGUCAUUGAGCAAGCACAGGGAAGUCAGCUUGUUCUCUCUGGCAGCGCUGGAAGACAGUCAACCUGUGGGUGGGGGGCUGCAGGGGGACAGGCCGCAGCCCUGCAGGAGGCCGUGCUCCGCAAUGGCUGCCCUAAGCUGCAUGGGUCAGACAGCUUCCCGUCUCGGGAGGCCACAGGGCAGGGAAGCUGCAGAGGGCAUGUGGCCCUGGGUAGGGCAGCUGCCCUUCACUCAUGCCCCUCCCAAGCAGAGGAGGGAAGGGCUUUAGUGAGAAUUCUAGCUCUGCCUCUUUGACCUUGCCAAGUCAGGAUCUGCCUCUUAAAGGAGCAGAGAAAACCAUCCCAGAUCCCCUCGACACCCAGCCCCCUACCACUGACAGAGCACAAGUGAGAUCUGAGUGUUAGCCCUUCAGAUUUGCUGACUGGCCUUGGCCCACCCCUCCCUGUGCUGCAGCUUCAUUGGCAAAAUGAAUUUGAUGGUAUCUGUAUCCCCUGCCCAGCCCUAACCUGUUUCUCUGAGGCUGGCCUCCCUACGGGGCUGCAGCAGCAAAGGGAAGCCAAGCCUUAGAGAAGCCUCAUGGAAGGGCCCAGAACAUCCUGCACCCAUCAGUUACUCGGAAGUAAGGGGACAAGAAGCAGCUGGAAGAGAGCUGGGUGUGGGGGCUGGGAGGAGUGCUGGAGAAAUUUCCCCAUCAGAAGGCCCCUCACUGGGCAGUGGAGGCAGGGCAGUGUGGUGGGACUGACUCAACAGACAUAGUUUCAUCUCCACCCUGCCCUUCUCAGGUUGUGUGACCCCAGCCACAUGGACACCCGAGUCUGUGAACUAAAGGGCUGGUCCAUGGCAUUAACAGUGGAGGGUGUCCAGGUUCUUGAUGUCUUGAACAAAGAAUUGGGCAAAAUGCACAAAGCAAGGAAGGAAUGAAGGGUUUUACUGAGAAUGAAAGUAUACUCCACAGCAUGGGAGAGGGCCUGAGCAUAGGGACUCAAGGGGCCCGUUACAGAAUUUUUGGGAGUAAAUACCCACUAGAGGAUUCCAUUGGUUACUUGAGGUACACCCUAUGUAAAUGGAAAGGAUGAAGUAAAUUUACAAAUUCAUUUACAGCAUAUACCCUAUGGGGAGGAUAUUCCCUGUUAUAGCUGAAGCGUGAAUUGGCCUUAUGUUCCCUGCCUCCAGACCCUAUUUUCCUGCAUCAACGGGAAAGGGUCAGAUUCACUGGCUCAGCUGUUUAACCUGUCCUGGUGCCAGCAGCUGGAGCUGGGUGUCAGGACCAGCCCGCAAGCUCUUCCCUGCCGGAAGGACCAGGCCAGUCGCUGUCCUUUUCAUGCUAGAGAGUGGUUGUGGUUGCUGACUUAGCAGAGAAGGUGCUUGGCUUUCCCCUUAACUGGAGAAAAAACUUUCUAAGAACCAGGCCUGGUUGGCAGCAGACCUAGCUUUCUUGGGGUGGCAGGGAGGCUAAAGCAUACCUCAGGACAGUCAGUGGUGGGUCCAGCUUCGGCUGGAGGUUCUUUCUACUGAAUAACUUCUACGGGCUCUGUCAUUAGCAGGAUUUGUAUAAUUUGAAGCAGAGCUGGGCAACUGCAGAGCAAUGGGGAAGCCAGCCCAGUGUGGUGGCAAGACCUGGGCAACUUGGGACCAGCCUGGGCUGUCUCUUGCCAGCUGUUGUUAUCAGAACCAGGCUCUUCACACUCAGAUCCUUGGGCCCCCCAUCUCAGAAUGCCCAGUGGUUGAAAGGAUGAAACCUGGAAUUUAAGUGACUUCUCAGUGAUGUGUGCCCUUCUCUGACGGUUCCUUGUUCAUCCCAUGUAUUUACUGACUGCCUGCUAUAUAUGCAGAGCCAAAGAGUGGGGCCUGGUCUUGAACUAUCUCCUCAUCUGCCCCUUCUGGCACCUCCUUCCUCCUGGGCUCUUUCCUCUAAUACCGUCAUCCUCUCUCCAACCUGGUUAAUCCUGUCCUUUCUGCCCUCAAAUGGGCACCUUCAAAGAAACAAAUAGAACUACUCCACUCGCUCCCUCUCUCCCUCCCUUUACUGCCACUAUUGAUUGUUAUAGUCACUUGCUCCAGGAAGUCCACUUGCUGAGUCUUACUGCAGACAGAGCCCACCCCCUGAGCUGUAAAGGCCCUAGGGCACAUGUUUGUCCAGCUGCCUCUUGCAGCUGGGAUUGUUAGGUCACUAUAGCGCUACCAACUGCAUAUACCACUGUGGGAGUCGUGCUGGUGGCGGUAGUGGUCACAGGUACCAGGGGCAGCAGUGAAGGGGUGGCUCUAAUGCCAAGUCCAGUGACCAGUGCCAGGGUGCCCAGUGGUGGCAACAGUGGUGUUUUCAGUGUGAUCUUGGACAUUGCUCCUGUCUACUCAGCUGCUAGUCUGUGAGCUCCCUGAUAUCCUUUAAGACAGCGUUUUCCAGCAGCGGCACUAUUAACGUUUGGGGCUAGGUAAUCGUUGGGUGUGUGAGUGUGAAGAGGGCUGUCCUGUGUGUUGUAGGCUAUUUUAGCAGCAUCCCGGCCUCUCCCUGCCAGGUGCCUGUAGCAGUCCCCCAGUUACGACAACCAAAAAUGUGUCCAGACAUUGCCAGAUGUCCACUGGGAGGGAAAACCUCUCUGGUCCACAGCCCUUCUCCUUAUUCCAGUCCCACAUCUUCCUCCCCUUCCCCAUCACUGUCCUCAGAGAGAUGCUGUUGACAGCUCCUUGAGGUGAUUCUCUCAGGCUUGUUGUUGUAGUUCUCUGCUGUCAAGUCUGAGCUGACUCUCUCUUCCGGAUUCUUCUUUCCUCACCUGCCCCCGUUUGCAUGAAGUUUUUUAUGGAGCUGUUUCUAUUUUCUUUUUGGGCAGCCAUACUCUCUAAGACCUAAAAGCUGAAUACUCGCCCGGUUACUACCUGAUAAUUCUCAUCGCUUAUGUUUCCAAAACCAAACUGGUUAUUUCCCUCUCUAACCCCAUCUCUGUGUCAAACAGUGGAGUACAUGCUUUUGGUUAAUCCAAUUGGAAGGCUUCCUAGAGGAAGUAAUAUCUGAACUGAAUCCUGAAAGAUUAGGGGAAGAGGAAGAAAAGGACAGGUGCUGUGGGAAAAAGGGGAAAGUGUCAGAGGAAGUAAAUGAAAAACCAUAUACAAAAUUAUCUUCUGUGACCCGUAGCACAUGCCCAAUCCAUGGUAGAUAUCGAAACAUAGUGGUUACCCAGUCUAAUCCAUCCCUUUUCUUUCUUUCUUUCUUUUUUUUCUUUUUUUUUGAGACAAGUCUCACUUUGUUGCCUGCCUGGAGUGCAGUGGUGCGAUCUCGGCUCACUGCAACCCCCGCCUCCCGGGUUCAAGUGAUUCUUCUGCCUCAGCCUCCUGAGUAGCUAGGACUACAGGUGCUUGCCACCAUGACCAGCUAAUUUUUGUAUUUUCAGUAGAGAUGGGUUUCACCAUAUUGGCCAGGAUGGUCUCGAUCUCUUGACUUCGUGAUCUGCCUGCCUCGGCCUCCUAAAGUGCUGGGAUUACAGGCGUAAGCAACCGUGCCCGGCUGUCCAUCUCUUUUCAGAUGAAGAGCUCAGGUUCUGAGGAGUGACUUGUCAAAAGCUGUUCUACCUCUCAGAGCCAGCCCUUGUCCUCCUGCUAGCCAGAGCAAGGUACCACCUGGAAGAGAUGUUCAGUUACAUGGGAUCCAGGGCCAGAGGGAAAAUAUCAGUGCUUCCUGAGGUUCGGGUCCAGCCACCCUUCUUCCACCAUUUCUACUGAGCCUUCAGUUGUACCCCUUCAGUCCACUUGGCGAGGCAUCACGCCCUCUGGGCAGGCUCAGUGGGGAACUAUGGGAGCAGGUGCUGUGUGCCACCUCUGGAGGGGGUCACUGAGGUUCUGGGUUGUGGGGGGUGCCCUGGGCCAGAGUGAGUUGUAUGGGAGUUGUUGCUGAAUCCCCCCAGAGUACCAGUCACACACCAGUGUGAGGGGCCUUGCAAGAGCCACUGGGCAGCACAGUUGAAGGUGGCACCUUCCUGCUCAGUGCUGUGUCCAGAGCAGGGUUUAGUUUUCUGUGUCUUUCAGGGUGAGACUGGUGUAUUCUAUACCAGCCUCCCUGUGUGUGAACAAUGACGAGAACAAUGUUGUCUUGCUUUCCCAAAAAAUAAGACACUAUCUAUUUCUCAUUAGUUAUACACGUUCAUUAUAAAACGUAAUUUAAGCAAUACUGAAAUGCCAAAAAGAAAGUAAAAUUCACUCCAAAAGUAAAAUUCACCCCAAAUCUCACUACUCCUGUAACUAUGUCUGACAGCCAGCUGUUGGGUCUUCCAUCGUUUUUAACCUUCAGGUGAGCACACAGAUCCUUAUUUUUUCUUUUCUUUUCUUUUUUUUUUUUUUUUUUUUUUGAGACGCAGUCUCCUGUUGCCCAGGCUGGAGUGCAAUGGCGCGAUCUCUGCUCACCGUAACUUCUGCCUCCCGGGUUCAAGCAAGUCUCCUGCCUCAGCUUCCUGAGUAGCUGGGAUUACAGGCAUGCACCAUCACGCCUGGCUAAUUUUUGUAUUUUUAGUAGAGACGGGGUUUCACCAAGCUGGCCAAGCUGGUCUCGAACUCCCGACCUCAGGCAAUCCGCCCACCUCAGCCUCCCAAAGUGCUGGGAUUACAGGCGUGAGCCACCUUGCCCGGACUCUCUUUGUAUUUUUUCUUUCUUUUUUUUGAGACAGAGUCUUGCUCUGUCUCCCAGGCUGGAGUGCAGCGACAUGAUCUCAGCUCACUGCAGCCUCUAUCUCCCAGGUUCCGGCAGUUCUCCUACCGGUUAGCUGGGAUUACAGGCAUGCGCCACCACACCCGGCUAAUUUUUGUAUUUUUAGUAGAGACGGGGUUUCACCAUGUUGGUCAGGCUGGUCUCCAACUCCUGACCUCAAAUGAUCUGCACACCUCGGCCUCCUAAAGUGCUGGAAUUACCGGUGUGAGCCACCGCGCCUGGCCAGAUCCUUAUUUUUUCAAUUGCAAUACAGCAGUAUGCAAGGCACUUACUGUAUGCCAAAGCUUAUGCCGAGAGCUGGCUGCCAGCAGCUCCUCCUGCCUCGAGGCCUUUGUCCAUGUCAUCAUUUCCCCUUUGGCUGUAACAGCUGCAGUUCUCUCAUAAUUUUAGGUUUCAUCUUAAAUGUCACUUCUUCAGAGGCUUCUUGACAGCACAAGUCAGGGCCCUUGUUAGUUUCAUCACAUCCAUUACCUUUCCUUGAUCACUUGUACCAUCAUCUGUAAUUUAUUUUUAUGUUUAAUACGGGUGUGGGAUUUCUGAUUUUUUUUUUUGCUAGACUGGAAGCUCUCAGAGGGCAGGAACCAUUUGUUUCCCUGCCACAGAGAUGUUCAAUAAAUAUUGUCAAUUGAAUGUGCAAAUAAUCUCACUUAACCACAGCUAUGAGGGAUGCUAUUUUAUCCCCAUUUUAGAGAUGACUAAACUGAGGCUUAGAACAAUUAACCCAAGGUCACAGUGAAUUAGUGGAUCCAUGUGUCUGCCUCCACACAGCCUGUGUGUUCUUAAUUAUUGAUCACUAAGCAACAGCUGCCUCUCACAAACUGGCAGGAAACUUCAACUUUUCCCUUUUAUCAAUAUAUUGUGAACGCCUUUUCUUGCUAAUAAAUAUACAUUUGUGUGCGUAA